CAAAGUGGCUGGUGCCAAACAACUAGCAGAGGCGCAAAAGUAGCCUCCCUGCGCUGGGAGCCCAGAGCAGGAGGCAGAGCCCGCGGGAAGCUCGGAGCACUCAGGACGCCGCGCGCCCUUCCCCGCCCUCCCUGACCAGGGAGCAGCUCGCUCCAGGCGCCCAGCCGAGGCCCCCAGCCCAGUGGGAGCAAGUCAUAGAGAACAAUUCGAGAGACAGAGAGACGGAGCGCGCUUUCCUGCUCAGUCCUGAAAAGUGAGCCGCUCCCGGGUUUGCAACCUCAAGCUUCGCAGCAGCGGCGGCGGCGGCUGCCGGGAAGGAGGCAGGUGCAGGUGCAGGAGGGAGGCGGCUCUGGGCUCCGCGCCUGGGUCUCGGCCAUGGCCUCGGUCCUGGGGAGCGGCAGAGGGUCUGGAGGGCUGAGCAGUCAACUCAAAUGCAAGUCCAAGAGGAGGAGGAGGCGGAGGUCCAAGCGGAAAGAUAAAGUAAGCAUAUUGUCAACCUUCCUCGCUCCUUUCAAGCACCUGAGUCCUGGCAUCACAAACACGGAGGAUGACGACACCCUCAGUACCAGCAGCGCGGAGGUGAAGGAGAACCGCAACGUGGGCAACCUGGCCGCGCGGCCACCGCCCUCCGGGGACCGGGCCCGGGGCGGCGCGCCCGGCGCGAAGAGGAAGCGGCCGCUGGAGGAGGGGAAUGGGGGCCACUUGUGCAAACUGCAGCUGGUCUGGAAGAAGCUGUCGUGGUCGGUGGCGCCCAAGAACGCGCUGGUGCAGCUGCACGAGCUGAGGCCGGGCCUGCAGUACCGGACAGUGUCGCAGACGGGCCCGGUGCAUGCCCCGGUCUUCGCGGUAGCGGUGGAGGUGAACGGGCUCACGUUCGAGGGCACAGGCCCCACCAAGAAGAAGGCCAAGAUGCGCGCGGCGGAGCUGGCACUCAGGUCCUUCGUGCAGUUCCCCAACGCCUGCCAGGCGCACCUGGCCAUGGGCGGGGGCCCGGGCCCCGGCACGGACUUCACCUCCGACCAGGCCGAUUUCCCCGACACGCUCUUCCAGGAGUUCGAGCCCCCGGCGCCGCGCCCCGGACUCGCGGGAGGCCGCCCCGGGGACGCCGCGCUUCUGUCCGCGGCCUACGGGCGACGGCGGCUGCUGUGCCGCGCGCUGGACCUGGUGGGCCCGACCCCCGCCACCCCCGCGGCCCCGGGCGAGCGCAACCCCGUGGUGCUGCUGAACCGCCUGCGCGCCGGGCUGCGCUACGUGUGUCUGGCAGAACCGGCCGAGCGGCGCGCGCGGAGCUUCGUGAUGGCCGUGAGCGUGGACGGCAGGACGUUCGAGGGCUCGGGGCGCAGCAAGAAGCUGGCCCGGGGUCAGGCCGCGCAGGCCGCACUGCAGGAGCUGUUCGACAUCCAGAUGCCCGGCCACGCGCCCGGCAGGGCCAGGAGGACGCCAAUGCCGCAGGAAUUCGCAGACUCCAUAUCCCAGCUGGUCACACAGAAGUUCCGCGAGGUGACGACGGACCUCACGCCCAUGCACGCCCGCCAUAAAGCGCUGGCAGGAAUCGUCAUGACCAAAGGCCUGGAUGCUCGGCAGGCGCAGGUCGUGGCCCUGUCCUCGGGGACCAAGUGCAUCAGCGGCGAGCACCUCAGUGACCAGGGGCUGGUGGUGAAUGACUGCCACGCGGAGGUCGUGGCCCGGCGGGCGUUCCUGCACUUCCUCUACACGCAGCUGGAGCUGCACCUGAGCAAGCGGCGCGAGGACUCAGAGCGAUCGAUAUUCGUGCGGUUAAAAGAAGGUGGCUACCGGCUGCGAGAGAACAUCCUCUUCCAUCUCUACGUGAGCACCUCCCCCUGUGGAGACGCAAGACUCCACUCUCCCUACGAGAUCACCACAGACCUGCACAGCAGCAAACACCUCGUCAGGAAGUUCCGCGGGCACCUGCGCACCAAGAUCGAGUCCGGGGAAGGGACGGUCCCCGUGCGUGGCCCCAGCGCAGUGCAGACCUGGGACGGCGUCCUGCUGGGGGAGCAGCUGAUCACCAUGUCCUGCACGGACAAGAUCGCCAGGUGGAACGUCCUGGGGCUGCAGGGCGCGCUCCUGUCCCACUUCGUGGAGCCCGUGUACCUGCAGAGCAUCGUGGUGGGCAGCCUGCACCACACGGGCCACCUCGCACGCGUCAUGAGCCACCGCAUGGAGGGUGUCGGCCAGCUGCCCGCCUCCUACCGGCACAACCGGCCUCUCCUCAGCGGCGUGAGUGACGCCGAGGCGCGCCAGCCGGGGAAGUCGCCCCCCUUCAGCAUGAACUGGGUCGUGGGCAGCGCGGACCUGGAGAUUAUCAACGCCACCACUGGGCGGAGGAGCUGUGGGGGCCCAUCCCGGCUCUGCAAGCACGUGCUGUCUGCACGGUGGGCGCGGCUGUAUGGCAGGCUGAGCACACGGACACCCAGCCCUGGAGACACGCCCUCCAUGUACUGUGAGGCCAAGCUGGGGGCGCACACCUACCAGUCUGUGAAACAGCAGCUGUUCAAGGCCUUUCAGAAGGCUGGCCUGGGCACCUGGGUGAGGAAACCACCGGAGCAGCAGCAGUUUCUACUGACUCUCUAGGCUGCGGGCUCCUGGCUGCUGGAGCUGAGCGGGACGCUGGAGGGAUGGGACCGUGUCUGGGGGGCGACGUGGCGGGUCGGCCGGUUCCCUGCAUUCGUUUUACUUUGGUGUCCCAGAAACACGCGAGUGUGCAAUGUUUGGACGAGCAACAACACAAAUUCAGAACGUGCCUCUUUCCAGAUCGCUGGCCCCAGAACCCUGUCCCCCACACCCAGGGGCACAUGCACUGUUGAGUUAGCGCCGACUCUUCCUGUGGAGUCUGAGGGAGGGGCUCCAUUCAGGCAAAGGGGUUUUAGCUGCAGCCUUGGAAGGAGGCACCGACACGACACCAGGCAGGAGUGAGCCUCAGGCCCCGUCCCUGCACCCCACCCCUGCGUGCGCCUCUUGGUGAUGCUGGGGUCUCACUAGCUUGAGGGGGCACAUGAAGAUAAGCCACAAAUGAAGAGAAAAGCCAUGCCCACCCCAGCCCCAGAGAAACCAAUAAGAAUCCUCUAUUAUUUUCACUAUUCAUUUAGGUUUUUAUACUCCACCUCCUUUCAAAAAAGAUUUAAGAUGUACGACAUUACCGAACACCUAAAAUAGAACCAGAGAAACGAAAGCCAUUCCCACAAAGUGAAGGAACAGUUUCCAAAACCCCUGCGAGGCAGAGUUAAGACCUGUGACGUGGGGAGCCUGGAAACACCCGGCCCACGCGUGCUGCAGAUGUGGGGAGCCUGGAAACACCCGGCCCACGCGUGCUGCAGAUGUGGGGAGCCUGGAAACACCCGGCCCACGCGUGCUGCAGAUGUGGGGAGUCUGGAAACACCCGGCCCACGCGUGCUGCAGAUGUGGGGAGCCCGGAAACACCUGGCCCAUGCCUGUUCAGUCCGUCAUGGCGUUUGGUUUAUGGUGGCCGAUACUAAGAGCCACUGAGGUCUGGGUUGUGUAAGGGUUAGCUACCACCCUAUAACCUCCCUACCAGGUAAUAAGGAGACCAAGUCUUUGAUCAAAUUCUGAUUUUUUAACUAAAUUUUCAUUAGAAAGCAAGCACAAAAUAAAAUCAAAACAACCUUUACCUUCAGCUUGAGAGGCUACCAGCUCUCUAUUCUUUCAGAUUCUCCAAUCAACACCUUGCAGGACAAGACCCCAAAAAAGUUCAGCUGUCAAAAAAUGUAAGAGGCAGGAUUCUGUGACCCUCAGAGCAGGCUUCCAACACCAGAGACCUUCAGCUCACAGUGGAGAUGGGACAUGGGGGCUUUAGCCCACAGCAUCAUCCCUGAGAGCCAAGGCGCUGUAUUCAUACGGGGUCAGGCUCUUUUCCAAGUAUCUUUACGUAAUCCAUGUACCUCGAGCUGCUGUCAUCUCACCUCCGAGAACUCAUUUCUAACAUUCAUCAUGCUAGAUAGCCAGUCUCUCAUUUCUCCAACUUAAAAAAUCCAUCUCUGAAAUUCAUGACAGUGAUGGCAGACGGCAAAGCAUGGUGGUGUCCACCUCUGGGGUGUGGGCUUCCCGGAAAGAAUCCCAGCUGACCACCCCAGAAAGUGCAAGAAUAACAUUGUGCUGUACAUAGUCAAGUGCUAUAAAUUACAGUUAUCAUAAUGAGAAGGCAGAAAUGAAACUGAGUUGUAGCUAUUUGUUACAAGAUAAUAAGAAGUAGAGAUAUUAGUAUGGAAAAAGAAACUUUUCCUGGGAUUUAAAAUCAGGCCAAAUUUAUCACUCGAGUUCUUUUAGAAAAGAAAACAGGUACUGGAGUAGACAACUUCUUCCAGAUAAAGUUUCAAAAGAUACGAGAACAUUUUUUCAAAUAAAGGACUCACAUUAAUCUUUUAUAAAAAUCACAAAAAUAAAUGAAAUCUUAAUUCAGUGCAAAAGCUAAGCUCAAACGACCAGUUUCUAUUAAGUUCUGGUAACUUGACAUCACUAGGAUGAAGCUUAGAGAACUUAGAGUCGAGAGGUGAUGGGUGGCUCAGACAUUCGCAGCAGUCAGAAGUGAGCGCUCCCCUGAAUGCGUGGGAGCACGGCCAGCUCCUGGCUGAAGUCUCCCACCCAGGCCUCAAAUCACCUUCAUCUGAGAUGUUGGCUAGAGAAGCAUAUAAUGCUUUGUCCCAGUGGGCUCCAAAUCACGCUGUUUCUGCAGCGAGGGGGCCUGUGUUGUAAGCAGAUUUCACUGUCACAGGGAAGACGCAGGGUCUGAUUCACGGGACUCGGAAAGCGCUCGGCCACCCAGUGGCCAGCAUCAUGAAGCCACAGCUGGGGGGUUGGGAUUCGUUUUGUCUCAGGCAUUGACCUUCCAGAAACAACUCAGACUUUACUGAAAUAUCAACAUCCACAUCUGGAGAAAGCCACACAUUAAUUCCAUGCUACCCAUUAGUACAAGUGUAUGGAUUCGUGUAUUAAGUCCACAGGAGACUCCAUGGAAGGAGAGAUUAAAGCUCUUCAGAGAAGGCCGAUAGCGACAGAAGAGUUUCCAAUGCAGCCAGAGUGAGGUUGAGGUGCCGGAGCCUUUCCGUGGAGGGAUCUGUCAGAGGGGAUGUGGGCUGCAGAGGGGACCCCACGUAAGGAAAGGAGGGUCCCAGGCCCUGGGUAGUGAAAGGAGAAGGUAGUCGAGGCAGUCAAGGGUGACCCUACACGCAGGAGGCACGCCACACCAGAUCACGCCACACGCAGGCUGCUCCCAACUGGCAGGGCCUGACCCAGCCAGGAAGGGCCAGGUCCUAGGAUUCCACAGUGCCAGGAGUGCCCGAAGGGGCCAGGUCCCAGGAUUCCCACAGCCCCAGGUGUGCCUGGAAGACCCGGGUCCCAGGAUUCCCACAGCCCCAGCUAUGCUUGGGGGGGCCGAGUCCCAGGAUUCCCACAGCCCCAGGUGUGCCUGGAAGACCCGGGUCCCAGGAUUCCCACAGCCCCAAGAGUUCCCGGAAGAGCUGGGUCCCAGGAUUCCCACAGCCCCAGCUAUGCUUGGGGGGGCCGGGUCCCAGGAUUCCCACAGCCCCAGGUGUGCCUGGAAGACCCAGGUCCCAGGAUUCCCACAGCCCUGGAUGUGCCUGGAGGGGCUGUGCCACCUCUGCAGAGAUGGAAGGGCUCGUGUUGAAGCCUGAGGAUUUCGCCCUCAGGUCCAGGUCAGAACAUCCCAGCACCACUUUCAGGCCAUGUCUGCCCUGCAGUUUUGACCACUGAAUUGGUCUUAAGAGUGGCCACCCAUUCCCCUCCAAGUGAGGGGGCAAGACACAAGUAGGGGACGGGUCACUUUCUGUCACCCUGAAAAUACGCUGGGCACGACACAAGUAGGGGAUGGGUCACUUUCUGUCACCCUGAAAAUACGCUGGGCACGACACAAGGGGGGCUGAUGAAGUCAGGCCCGCCCCUCCAAGUCCACCUCGAAAUCACCGUCUGGCUUCCUCGCACUUCCCACCACCUGACACCGCCAAGCCCCUUGCUUCAGAUUUUCUGUGGUCUGUAUUCAUACCCUUGCUUCAGAUUUUCUGUAGUCUAUAUUCAUGCCUGCUUAGGCCCCUACAAAAGUCCUCAUAAAACCAGCACCACCUUUAUCUGCCUCCAAAACACACACUGCUUUCCCAUCAGGAAGAUCAGCAAUGUGGUUUCCGGCCUGGUUCUUAGUCAAAAAGUUAGUGUCUGGUGGUUUCUGGCCUUUUUGCAGGACGGGGCGCAGGGAACGGCUGCGCGGCCAGGCAGCCUCCGCUGUCCACCUCCAGCCCCGGUUUUGCAGCCGUGUGUGAUAUCAAGGGAUAGAGUUAGGGUUUCUGUGGGUUUUGUUUUUGCUGAGGAAAGGAUGUGCAGGUCGAUAGCUAUUGUUUCCUUUCCAUUCCUGUGAUUCUCUUUACAUCUGUAUAUAUCUAUCACACCAUGCUGACUUUGUGAUGAGUCCUGUUCCUCAGAAACAUCAAGCUGGGUUCCUUUUCAAAGAAACACACAGAUCAUAUUUCUCCAUCUCAUUUUGUUUUCACAGGGAGCUUUUCUUAUCAACAAAGUCGCAUGCUUUUUUUUUUGGAUAUAAUGUUUAUCACGUCUGGAGAGCCAUAAACAGUAAAUACAGAGGAUAUCAAUGCCCAGAAUAGUUAUUUUGAUGAAAUCCUAUUUUUAGAUAAUAAAUUUCAAGAUGUGUCUAUAGUGUAUUGUUUAAAACAACUGAAGACAUUUGAGACGUACAUAAAGUAGACAUUUUUAAUUUAGGGAAACUUAUAUGCCCUUUUUUAAGAAGCCAUUCUAAUAAAAUAAUCUGACUAAUUGGCCCAAAAUACAAUAAGUAUCACUUUCUAACAGAGACCAAAGGGAAGCUGAGAGGCUUUCCUUUUAUGUACUACCGUUGGAUCGCUGCAGCCGCCUCUCAUAACACCCAACAGAACCCGGUGAGGCUCUGUGGGCUUCCCGCGGCCCUCAGGGAGGCUGCAGAGUCCCCUAGUCCAUGUCAGGGAGCCGCCAUCCCACAUACCUCCAAAGCCUGUCCUCGCCUGCAGUUUUUGCAGAGCUCGCGGUUGGAGGUGGAAAUUUAGAAGCCCUGUGUUGCAGGAGAGGCAGUAGCACCCCCAGGCAGCUCUUAGCAGGGACAGACCACCCCCCGCCUCGCUGGUAUUUUAGGGUCUUUUGGUAUUUUGCCACUGUGUGGGGCUAGGCGGGUGGCUGGAGGACACGGUGUAGGCCUUGCCGCUGUCUGGGUUCCUCGCCACUGCAGGAGCAGGGCUGUUUCUGGAAACACUGGGCUGCUGGUGACCCGUCAAACUUCUCCCACAAAUUCUGAAUCCGAGAAAGUGAAGGAAGGAUGGUGGGGAAGUGAGGAGGCAGGAGCAGAGGCCACAGGGACCAACCAGAGAUGCGGUGGAGACAGAGGAGCUUCCUUCUCAGGCUGUUUCUGGGAAGCCUGAGAGGCGGCCAGCACCACCCUCCGCUCACUCUCCCCUCAGCCUCUUCGCUUCCCUUCUCAACCCUUUCUCUCCUCCUCGCCUCUUCCCUUUCUUGCUGUCUUGUUAGUCCCUGUCCCAAAACUCCUGGCUCCUUUGUUCUGCUGCCGUGGCCCCCACCCAGGAGGAGGUCUCAGGCACCAUCCCCCCACGAGGGAUCCACACAACAGGUUCAUGCUGGGGCUGGGGGAGCCCCGCUGGGUUCCUGAUGCCUUGUGCACAGGGAGUUGCUGCAGUCAUUUUUGGACUCUCCUGAAUGUGUCCACAUGUUCUGACCUCCCACCAGAAGGAACGCUGGUGGCCACAUCUCUAGAGAUCUAUUUACUUUUUUGAGACCGGCUUAUGAGAUUGGCUAAUUUUUGUAUUUUUGGUAGAGAUGGGGUCUCACCAUGUUGCCCAGGCUAGUCUCGAACUCCUGGCCUCAAGUGAUCUGCCCACCUCGGCCUCCCAGAGUGCUGGGAUUACAGGCAUGAGCCACCGCGCUGGCCUCUAGAGAUUCACACCAAACAAUAUCACUCCUGCGGGAACCGCAGACAGAUCAAACCCUGGUGAGAGGAACACUUUAUUUCCCAACUCAUCAUCCUAAGCCAAGGUUGGAGGGAUGAGCAUUCCCUAAACACCAAGGCGAGAUCACCUGGUCCCAGUGCCUCUUUUCACACAGGCCCUAGAUUUCUAUCUCUCUGCAGUUUAUGCAUCGGUAAAAAAAAAAAAAUCUCUCCCAGUGUGCCCCGUUAGUUUUCAGCAUUUUGUAAGCAAAAUGAACUUAACACAUAGUAAUUCUAAUUGAAGGUAUGUACAUAAAAAGCAUGAUAGAAUGGCAAUAUUGUAUCAAUGGAUGUACAUUUGUAAUAUUUGUAAAAAAAAAUCCAAAACCUUAAAAUAUGAAUUUACAUGUUAAUUUGCCUCUAAGUUCUAUAAAUUGCACUUCAGUGAUAUCUAAUAAGUGAAUGUUUCUGUUAAGUAAAUAAAAAUAUUCAGUAAAAUUGUU